AGUGCGCAGGCGCUGGCAAGAUGGCGGGAGGGGUGCUCCCGCUGAGGGGCCUCCGCGCCUUGUGUCGCGUGCUGCUCUUCCUCUCGCAGUUCUGCAUUCUGUCGGGCGGUGAGCAAUCGCAGGCGCUGGCUCAGUCAAUAAAGGAUCCGGGCCCAACACGCACAUUCACAGUAGUUCCCAGGGCAGCAGAAAGUACUGAAAUCCCACCUUAUGUGAUGAAGUGUCCGAGCAAUGGUUUGUGUAGCAGGCUUCCUGCAGACUGUAUAGACUGCACAACAAAUUUCUCCUGUACCUAUGGGAAGCCUGUCACUUUUGACUGUGCAGUGAAACCAUCUGUUACCUGUGUUGAUCAAGACUUCAAAUCCCAAAAGAACUUCAUCAUUAACAUGACUUGCAGAUUUUGCUGGCAGCUUCCUGAAACAGAUUACGAGUGUACCAACUCCACCAGCUGCAUGACGGUGUCCUGUCCUCGGCAGCGCUACCCUGCCAACUGCACGGUGCGGGACCACGUCCACUGCUUGGGUAACCGUACUUUUCCCAAAAUGCUAUAUUGCAAUUGGACUGGAGGCUAUAAGUGGUCUACGGCUCUGGCUCUAAGCAUCACCCUCGGUGGGUUUGGAGCAGACCGUUUCUACCUGGGCCAGUGGCGGGAAGGCCUCGGCAAGCUCUUCAGCUUCGGUGGCCUGGGAAUAUGGACGCUGAUAGACGUCCUGCUCAUUGGAGUUGGCUAUGUUGGACCAGCAGAUGGCUCUUUGUACAUUUAGCUGUGGUGUGUGCUUCAGAAAGGAGCAGGGCUUAGAAAAAGCCCUUUUGUCCGUAGGAGUUGAUGUGGUGUGAGUGAUAUAUUUCUAUGUUUUUAAUGUACAGCAUCUGUACUUUGUUUGCCUUGAUAAAGGUAAGAUAAAUGAAACGCUGAACUAUGCUAAUCUGGAAUUUGUUUUUAUUUGCCUGAAAUAUAUUUUUUUCUGUGAAAAAAUUAAAACGUACUUAAGCCAGGAGAAUGAAUUAUACAGUGAUUGAAAAUCCAUUUAAUUCCUAUGACUUUUGUUUUGUAUUGCCCAAGUCAAACUACAUCACUUGUAUCUCCAGCCCAAAUGUAGUCUGCCUUGAAAAGUCUUUCAGCUGUGACUGCAGGAAGUGGGAGUGUUUUUAUUGUUAGCUAAUUGCUGUGACUGCAGGAAGUGGGAGUGUUUCUGUUGUUGGCUAAUUGAAGUUAUUAGGCUCAGCUUCAGUCAUGUGUAAGUUUUGCAGUGUAAUACAUAUGUAGUCUGGUCUGUAUAUAUGAAAAUUUGAAUUAAACUGCAGAAUGUUUAUGUCUAGUUAUGGUUUAAAUUUUCUUAGUAGUAUAUAAAAGGUAAGAGUACUGAAAAAUUAAUAAAAUUGCAAGUUAAGAAA